AGUCACAUAGCUGUGUGGUACGUGACUGGAGGCAUAUCACUGUCCUCGCCUGGAUCACGCCAAUGUGACCCCAACCCCACCACCCUCCCCACCCCAUGAUGUCCGAAAAAACCCAACAAAGAAAAUUGGCUGGGACCAAGAAAAAGUUUACAGACUAUCAUCAGUGGAACAGUGCUGGUGUUGGUACCGGAGCAACCGACACCAAAAAGAAGAAAAUAAAUCAUGGCGCUAACCCUGAGACAACCACUUCGGGGGGCUGCCACUCGCCUGAGGAUAAACAACAGAACCGAGCUCAGCUGAAAGAGGAAAAUAAGGCAAGCCACCAACAUCAGCAAGCCCUAAGGAGGCAGCUAGAGGCCCAGGAUCAUACCAUACGAAUCCUUAUGUGUCAGAAAACUGAACUGGAGACAGCGCUCCAUGACAGCCAGGAUGCUGCCAGGAAAUUUGAAGAAGAUUCCAAGGAUCUGGCAGCCCGCCUGCAUCAUUCCUGGCACUUUGCAGGAGAGUUACAGCGGGCUCUCUCUGCUAUGUCCGCAGAGCACGAGAGGGCGGACAAGUACAUCAAGGAGUUAACAAAGGAGAGGGAAGCCAUGAGUCUGGAGCUGUUCAGGAACAUCAUAACCAAUAAGGAGCUGAAGGAGAAAAAUGCCGAACUACAAGAAAAACUUCGACUGGUAGAAACUGAAAAGUCUGAGAUCCAGCUCCACAUCAAGGAGCUAAAAAGGAAACUGGAGACGGACAAAAUCCCGCUGCCACAGGUUCAAACCAACACUUUGCAGGAGAAGAUGUGGAGGCAGGAGGAGGAGCUACGGGAUCAGGAGGAGCUACGGGAUCAGGAGAAGCUACGGAAGCACGAGGAGAAGAUGUGGAGACAGGAGCAGAGGCUGCGGGACCAGGAGAAGGAGCUGCGGGAGCAGGAGCAGCAGAUGCAGGAGCAGGAGGAGCAGAUGCGGAAGCAGGAGGAGCAGAUGCGGAAGCAGGAGGAGCAGAUGCGGAAGCAGGAGGAGCAGAUGCGGAAGCAGGAGGAGCAGAUGCGGAAGCAGGAGGAGCAGAUGCGGAAGCAGGAGGAGCAGAUGGGGAAGCAGGAGGAGCAGAUGGGGGAGCAGGAGGAGCAGAUGCGGAAGCAGGAGAAGCAGAUGCUGAAGCAGAAGGAGCAGAUGCGGAAGCAGGAGGAGCAGAUGUGGAAGCAGGAGGAGCAGAUAGGGGAGCAGGAGGAGCAGAUGCGGAAGCAGGAGGAGCAGAUGUGGAAGCAGGAGGAGCAGAUAGGGGAGCAGGAGGAGCAGAUGCGAAAGCAGGAGGAGCAGAUGUGGAAGCAGGAGGAGCAGAUGGGGGAGCAGAUGAGGAAGCAGGAGGAGCAGAUGGGGGAGCAGGAGGAGCAGAUCCGGAAGCAGGAGGAGCAGAUGGGGGAGCAGGAGGAGCAGAUGCGGAAGCAGGAGGAGCAGAUGGGGGAGCAGGAGGAGCAGAUGCGGAAGCAGGAGGAGCAGAUGGGGGAGCAGGAGGAGCAGAUGAGGAAGCAGGAGGAGCAGAUGGGGGAGCAGGAGGAGCAGAUGGGGGAGCAGGAGGAGCAGAUGCGGAAGCAGGUGGAGAGGCUGCAAUUCAAGGAGGAGAGGCUGUGGGAUGAGUAUGAGAAGAUGCAGGAGGAGGAGGAGAAGAUCCGGAGGCAGGUGGAGAAGAGGCGGGAGAAGAAGGAGAGGAUGGGAGAGCAGGAGAAGACGCAGGAGGAGCGGUGCUCAGAGCCCUGCCUCCCUCCCUCCAAAUAUCCUUCUGAUAUGAGCCACCCUGGCAGCCUGGAGCCUGCACGAGAGGCCGGGAAGGGUUAUUCCCAUGACAACCGCACUGCACAGAUCAUGCAGCUGCCCCCUGGAAUGAAGAACGCCCAGGAGCGCCCAGGCUUAGGCAGCACCUCCUGCAUCCCAUUCUUCUACGGAGGAGACAAGAAAAAGAUCAAGAUCAUCAGUAUCUAAAAAGAACGGUCAACAAGGCCUACAGAAGUGUAAGCCGCCAUGUGACCUUGUGAAUACAGUCUGAGAACAAACUUGAAAAAAAGAAAAUUUAUUUUAAAUUGUGGCAAAAUACUGGCCGGGCACGGUGGCCUGCACCUGUAAUCACACCACUUUGGGAGGCCUAGGCGGGUGGAUCACCAAUCCCAGCUACGUGGGAGGUUGAGGUUGCAGUGAGCUGAGAUCACACCACUGCACUCCAGGCUGGGUGACAGAGUGAAACUCCCAUUUCAAAAAAAAAAAAAAAAAUUCUACCUGAGGACUCUAAUAUCUAUGUAUGUUUCUAUUGUUUUUUUUGUUUGUUUUCUCCUUUUGUCUUGCGUUGUCUUGUCUUAUGGCAUGCCUAGUAAAGUUUUAUCUGCCUCCA